GCAAACCUCCCGGCGCGGCCAUGCGGGGAGGUAAGUGAUCUGCCUGUGCGCCCAGGGCGUGGGAAGGCGCCCGCCCUCUCCUCUCUCCAGGAUGAAAGGAAACGAAGAAUGCCGCAAUGAAAACCGCUCUGCCCUCCCAAAAACACAUCUUGGCCGUGUGUCCGGUGCUCCUGCAGCUCGUUGCACCCACGGACGUGGGCUCUCACUGUGGAGUGGAGUGGGGGCAGAAGCGUGCCCUGCCCCACGGAGAGCCCCGGCUCGCCUGGGGCUGCUGGCAGUGCUCGGGGAGCGGGACGGGGUGGUGGCACGACUCGGCGGGGACCCCGAGAACGCCACACCUCCACCCUCCACUUUCCAAAGACCGGCUUCCCCGGGGAGCCCCCACACUAAACGCCAGCGAACUGCCUCUCCGUGAAAGUCUUAGCCAGAAACUUUCCCCGCUUUGUCGCCAGUGCCACAGAGAGUCGUGUGGCUCUGGGCCGGCGCUGCUGGUCCAAGAGGCAGCCUGGCGUCUUCUGCCCCUACCGUCCCCUUCUCAGGCCAGUUCUCACUUGCCCCUGAGACGCCAUUCCCGGCUCGGUGAGGUCGGCCCUGCCCUCGGGCGACUUCAGGCUGGCUGCACCGGGGGUCGGAUCCCGGGAGGCAGGGCCGGCGGCUCCUUUGGGACCGCGCUGGCUCCCUAGGCGAGUCCUUUCUGCCUGGGGGACGAAUGCUGAUCUAGAAAAGAAGCCAAUCAAAGUCAACAGCUUCCCGCCCUUCCUAACCGCCUCCCCUCUCCCUAUCUGAGCGCAUUCCCAAGUGGGUCGACAGUUCUGCUCCAGAAUACUGACACCAAAGUUAUUUCAGCAUAUAAUUUGGAGAUUUCAGGAUCUCUAAAGUUAUUUCAGCAUAUCCCAUAAUGUGCUGGAUCGGAAGGUCUUGUUUGGUUGCCUCUCCCCCUCACCCCCACACACCACAUACACACACACCCCCACAUACGUACCACACCCACACACAAAGUACACCACAUAGUGCACACAUCACACUCACAUACUUUAUGCUACAUACUACACACACAACUUUUUAUCAGCAGAGGAUUGAUGGCAAACAGUUUGUUGGAGGGAGUGUUUGCUGAAGUAAAGGAACCCUGCAGCCUUCCCAUGCUAUCUGUUGACAUGGAAAACAAGGAAAAUGGCUCUGUCGGUGUAAAAAAUUCCAUGGAAAAUGGGAGACCACCUGAUCCUGCAGACUGGGCCGUGAUGGAUGUCGUCAAUUAUUUCCGAACCGUGGGAUUUGAGGAGCAAGCUAGUGCUUUUCAGGAACAGGAAAUUGAUGGAAAAUCCCUGCUAUUGAUGACAAGAAAUGAUGUGUUGACAGGACUUCAGUUAAAAUUGGGGCCUGCUCUGAAAAUCUACGAAUAUCAUGUAAAACCUCUGCAGACAAAGCAUUUAAAGAACAACUCUUCAUAGUACAGUCAAAUUGGGGUCUUCGACCUCAAAAAAUACAUAAUGACAUAAUUUAGUUUCAUGUAAUGAAACUUUGUAAACAGAAUACAUACAUGUGUAUAUGUAAAGAAUUUCAAUCAAAUGAAACGUUAUCCUAUUGGAUAGACUAGGCAAUUCAUCAGCUCACCUGAAAUCAGCCAGGAGGAGCAAGGACAAGAUGCGCACAGGGUGGUUUUCCUCAUGGAUUUUGUCAAAUAGAUGAUCUUUGACACGAUUAGACACUCCUCCCCACAAAGGCUUUGAAAUCAUAAGGAUUUUCCUCAUCUCUUUAUAGCUUUCCCAAAAUCUUUUAAAAAAGAAUUUAAUUAAAUGACAGUCUUUUGGUUACAGACUUAGGAUGAGUAAAAACAAGAAAAUUUGGGGAGGGGGAGAAAGAAGAAAGGGAUUGCUGUCUCCCUUGAAUUCCUCUGUUCCUUAGAGCUUGUGUUACUUGGACGGAAUUGCCAACACCCUUUUUUAUAGAGGGUUCUCCACUUGACCUUAUUAAGGUUUUAUUGGGAUAUGCUGCAGUGUUUGAAAUGAACAUGCAUCAUGGCCCCUUCAGGAGCAGAAUCAUAGCUCUGAAAAGAGAAGCUCCGUUGUGUACUGAGGAUAUCCAUCCAUAUUCAGCUAGCUUUCAAAUGGGGUAACGAUAUUUUCUGCAUAGAUUUUCUUUUAAAUUGGUUCUUUGUUUCUGAAGAAAGAAUUUUUUUUAACUUCAUGGUUUUAUUUAUAAUAAUUUGUUUCUGAAGAAAUUUGCCGAGAGUUACAGGUCAAAAAGCCUUGUUACUAGUACAGAAUAUUUUUAUAUAUAUUCCUUCAUGAUGGUGUAAUUUUUUUUAAUUGUCCUAUGCUUUGUUCGGUUCCUGGGUUAAGUACUUGUUUUUAAGAGCUUGGAAAAAGUGGGCUUGCUACAUCUCUGUUCAAAGAGACAUUUGUUCAAUCUCUGUGUGUCAACGCCUUGUUGAAUUGGUGCUUUGUGGUUGCAAUAAAGCAUUGCUUCAGUUUA